GGUUGGAAGGUUCACAGGAGAUUCAUAAGACUUGCUGUCACCGGUUAAUUUUCAUAGCAUGCAUGCUUAAAUGUCUAUUUUUGGUCUGUUUAUUCUGUUUCUUCACUACACAAAGUCAUGUAAAACAUGAUAAAUUGGACCUUAUGAAACCUAAUUAAAUCAAUGAGUGUUCUACUCCUUUAUGUGGAAACCACAAGUAUGUUGUAAAAGUCGCCACUCCCUUAAUACGUGAACAAAAUCAAAACAUGCCAUAAUUCUAAGAUGUUUGAGCUAUAUUUCUGUAGCCCAUUUUGUGGUUAAGCCACCAGUGACAUGUCUGAAUAAGUAGAUUUGAUGGGUUGGCUUUUGGUUGUUAAAACCUGCCUCUCCACCUUCCCCUCCUUUCUUGUGAAGCAUAAUAGCCUUGUAUUGAAGCUCUUCUUUAUGUAUCCUCCUAGCCAUCUUACAGUUUUGACUUAUCAGAUAGGGAGGCAUUCAGCUGGGCUUUAUAAAUAAACAGUUUAUAUGUAAAGUUGAUGGGUUUAUUUGAUUUCUGGAAAAUUCAAAAAUAUAUACAAAAACUCAAAAAUCCUAAAAGUGGCUGAUACUUAAACAGAAGUGAAAGGCACAAGAGGUCAUAUAGUUGUGUCUCAAUACCUAUUCAGGGAAGAGAAUUAUUUCUGUAAUAUCAUAUUGCUUUCAUUAAGAUGGCCCUGGUCAUAAAGGUGGUGUCUACAAAUGGACCUGUCCAUAAAGGAUAUCAUUCAUUUUAUUUUAUUCUUUUGUAGAGUCCUUUUUAUACUUCACCAGGGAAUUCUGGCACAUUUUCUAAGUGAGUGUGAGCAGUUUAAGAACAUAUUUUGAUUAAUGAGUUUUGUGGACAUUAUGCUUUUUUUUUUUUUCAAAUAUAGUGUCCCAUAUGAAUUCUGCCUAGAGUGUAGUGUAUCUACUGUGAAAUAAAAGGGCAGAGGGGUCACUUGCUAUAAUUAAAGAACAGAGUCCAUUGUUGUCGGACAGCAAACUGUUUUGAAAGCUACAUAAGAGGUUUAGCUGUUAAAGACGUUGGUAACUAAGGGUGGCGUCCAAAUCAGCAUUGAUCCAGCUCCUUACUUUUCUAUAGGCCUCCUCACAGGGUGACAGGGCUUUUUGAGGGAGGGGGCUGCCCUUUCCCCAAGAACACAUGGAACUUAGGUAUUUGUGUAAUCAGACCCAUCACUGAAUUCUGACUUUGGUGUGUGAAAUCCGUUUGCUUUGCUGGAGAGAGAAGGAAUAUGCAUAACUGAUCAAGAUUGUCCUAUAGGAGAUAAAUAAUGUUUUGCAACUUUUAAUAACUUUGCAAAUAGUCUGUAAAAAACGGUGGGGGGAGGGAUUGAUAGUCCAAAUGUCGUGAGGUUAAGAAUGCUCUUCAAGUGAAAUUGCUUGGCUGCAAGAUGGUUUUAAUUAGACUGUUAUAAAGACUUAUUUUUCCUAAGCAGCAUUUUAUAGUUAGUAAAUGAAAUGUAUGCCGAAAGUGCUAAGCAGAAAUCUCCCUAACCACAGAGGUGUUCAAUAACCAGAUUCGAACAACAUGGAAAGUACCAUCUGUUCUUCGUUUUCAGCGUGAAAAAGAGGGAUUGAAUGGCUGCGAUUUGCUCCAGUUUCGACGGUGUCUGUGUGUGCGCGUGUAUUCUUUUUUAAUUUAAAAAAGUUCACCUGGUACUUCAUAGAAACUUGAAAUUGCAGUAAUAUGAGCAACACUGUGAAAACACAUGUUCCUGCAUUUAUUUUAACCAGUUCCACUUUUAUUUAAAAGAUUUCCAGAAGCCCAGCCAUUGAACACUUUAUAAUGGUUAUACAGUUCCUGCAGGCAAUCACAAUGAGCGGUCAGCUUUUCCAAAGAUCUGACUAUUUAGUCAGUACUUGAAUUAUUCUGUCAAUUUUCCCCCUGGAGGCAAGGAGGGGAAAAGGCUCUCACGCCAACUCUGGUCAGCGUUUAUCAGUUAAUCUAAUUGUGUGUGAUAUUGCUGUGGACUGGUGUUUACUAUACAUAGACCUUGCUCUUGUUCAGAGCUGUAAUCUAGGAUUGUUGAUAAUGAGGAAAAUAUCCUUUUAAGGAAGGGUAACUUUUGAGUCCUUGACUUUUAGACACUAAGAAUCUUGGUUCUGGGUUUAGUUAGAGCCCUGGGUAAAACAUUAUCCGGCCUUUGUUUGAGGUCUUUUAUUGAAGCUAAUGACUGGGCUUGUGCCUCCCUGAGAUAAAUGACAUUAUCUCUGAGUGGCCUGACAGGAAACAGACAUGUUAAUGGUGAAGCUGCGGGGAGGAUCUGCUUGGGUUCUGACAAAAGAGUCGAGAAAGGGACCCCUGGUUGUGGUCAUUAACACAUAAUGCAUUCUUGCUCUUCCUAAGAGGCCCUUGAUAAUUGGAAAGCUAUUUUAGCCACAAGCACUUAAAUCAUAAAUCUACUACUCCUAGUUCUUUGCAUUCUUAAAAGUAGCAAAGUAAUGUGUUUUUUGUUAACAAGUGUGUGAUCUGGUUUUUUAACGUGGUGGCAGCUCUAGGCUGCCUGGGUAAUGACGUGUGGGAGAGCUGCACGUUGAAUUGUUUUUAUCAGUUGAGAUCCUUCUUUGUCUUUCAGCAUUGCUCAGCCAUCCCUCUACUUUAAUAAAGUGAAAAGUGGGUACAGAGCUGAAAAUAAGUCAUUUUUAUGCUUGAAGAUGUCUUGUGGGAGGGGGAUAAAAUCUGUUUCAUAAGAUAUUGUGCAGUGAUUUGAAUGUGAUGAAACCUGACUUGGAGUGUAUGUUUUCAAAAGUCAUGAGUAUAAUUGAGUUUCAAUGCAGUUUAAACUCUCUGCUUCUUGAAGGAAGAUAAUUGCCACAUUGAACACACUCUAGAGGUGUAGAAGAGGUGGCAGGAUCAUGUUAUUCUAUUCUUUAAUAUUAAGCACUGGAAGUUUUUCAUAGUAAUUACUGCAGCACAACAUAGUUUUGAUUGCCAGCACUCUGAACUUGCCAGCAAUCUGAACAUCAAGGGUUUUGCUUGAAUACAAAACACUUUAUUCCUAAAUUACUUGUAUUACAUUCCUGUGUUAUAUGGAAGUCAGAACUAAGGAAAUACUGGGCUAUCCUUGUUAGCAACAUCUUAGGGAAAAUAACCCUUCUUCGCUAGGAUUCUUGUUGAUAAAUGAUCAUAAUACUCUCCUAAUGUAGUCAUUGAAGAUUAAAGGGAUGGAGAACAGGUGAGCUCCCUGCCUCAGUGAUGACUUAGACUGUCAUUAGAGAGUAAGUAAUAUGUGUAUGAUAUUGGUGCCCUGUAACUGGUAUGUCAUAGGUGUGUGUAUAUAAAUGUUGUAACUGCAUAUACAGAUGUUGGAUUGGGAGUAUUUAGUUAGUAUGGGUUUUAUUCUUUAAAAAAUGUUCACUGUUGGUUUUACGUUCCACUCUGUUGCAGAAUAUAUGGACCUCUCCCUCUGUGUCUAAUUCUUUCUCCCAACUGCAGUUUCACUAGUGACUACUUGCUCCCUGUCACAAGUUCUUUUUAAUUUAAGCUCAAGGUUUUGGCAAUGGGAACAAAGCCUUUGCAACUGAAUGAAAGGUUGUUAAACUAUUCAUAGUUGAUUGACCAGCAGUUGGGCUGUUUGUAAUGUUAUUUUGAGAGCUCAAAGGAUAUGCAACCUCUUGCAUAUCCAAAGUGAGACUUUGCUCCUAAAGCUGAAUUUUGCAUAUUUGCUAAAUUUUUCUUGGAAAUACCUUUGGGAAUGUAGUAGAAAAGAUGAUGGGUUUUGCCUUAAGAACUGAAAUGAUCACAAAGCAAAUACUUAUAUUUUGCUAGGUCUGUGGGCCUUGAACCACAGGGAUCCCAUCUGGUAUUCAGAAGGCUUUUCCCCCCAGUGAAACUAAAUGAAAACUUAAAGGUAUAUAUUGUAACUGUAAUAAAGAACUCAAAGGAAAAGGUGUUUCGGUUAGAACAAAUAGGUUUGAAAUGAUGAACAAAUACUUCUGUGGAUUUUUCAAAGCCACUUACUCUUCUUUCUCAUUUCCACCCCCCGACCUAGUUUGAAUAUCAUUCACUGUGACUAUUCCAACCCAACUACUGAGCUUUCUGCCUCCUGGGAAUCCUCAUUGUCAGCUAGCACCUUAAGAAAAAUGUGUCUGCAGGGACAUUUAGGCAUAUUCCAAUAAUGCCACAUGAAUGUAGCUUUUACAGUUUAAAAAGCAAGUAAAAAUAUAUUGAUUAUAUUUUGUGUUGUACAUAAUGAUUUCAGAAAGCAGAUAUUUAGGUUGUGGAAUUGGCUUAUUAUGCUAACCAGAGAGCAGAUGGCAUGGUGCCACAGACGUAUAAUUUUACUUAAAGGGACUUUUAAGGUUUUGAUGUGUUUUCUUUUCCUCUUAUUUCCCUGAUGGCUUCUUUUCAUUGAAGGGUAACUUAAGGAGACCUGGUAGCAAUUUUACUGCCUUCCCCUGACAGUUUGAAAUAAUAGCUUGGUCUUUGGUUGCACUGAUCUUCUACCAGUCAACUCGAUUCUGGUUUUUGUCAUGUGGCAGAGAAUUUUUAAAAAAAGUGUUAGUAGUAUGUUUUAAGAAGUGGACUCUUUUAUAUGCCUCAAUUAGCAACAGACGACAAAGUUCCAAUUGGUCACACUUUCAUAAACUCCUGGAAGUCACUGUUUGUCCUUUUGAUUAAAGAAAACUCCUGGUUUAGUUUCUUAGGAAAAGCACAUCUGGCCCUCUGGCCGCUUUUGGUAUACCUUUUUGUCCUUCGCAUUAGUCACUGAAGGUUCAAAGGUUGUGUCUAAGUUGUUCCUAGUUAGGUUAGAAAAUUUUCCCCAUGCUGGAGGAAAUGUACUUUUUUUUUUUUAAACUACACUCAUCAUGUGUUUGGAUUCAGCUGGCAUAAAAGUACCUUUUGUUUUUGUACCUAGAUUUUACAGUUUUAUCCAUUAUUCACCUCACACAUCAUCAGGAUGAGUUGGAAAGCAUCUUCUAACUUUUUUUUCCAAAGCGUGCAUAGCCAGACCAGUUUACUUCUGGAUUUCCUGUCACUUCCUUGGCUGAUUUUAUGGAUGGCUCAUGUUAAAAACAACAAAAAUGUUUGAACUGGAAGGGUUGAAGCCUUGGGUUUUCAUUCUUCAUGGAGAACUGUUUAUUUGUGUGUGGUUCACCACAGUACAUGGAUAAUGCUAUCAAAUCUGUGCUUUAUUAUAGGCUUAUGACUAGCACAGCCGCACUUUAGUUAUGUGUUCCCGUGCUUUAGUUAUUUGCCAAUUCUUUUGUGAUGGAAAUGAAAUUAGAGCUGAAUCUUUGCAACGAAGGGGAAAAUAGGCACAACAAAUAGAAACUAUCCCUUGAGCCAGUUAAGAAGUAAGCAGUGGUGAUUAAACAUGUUUUUUUUUUUUCAAAAUAAGUGAAACACAGAGGAAACUACUUCCUUUUAGCUUUUCUGUGAAGUUGUGUGGAAGAUGAGCUCAACAUUUUGAGAAGUGGAGGCUGCAGCUAGAUUUUAUCCCCUUGUAUCGUUUGACAUCUUCAGUAAUUGAAAAGCGAUUCGUAUUCCCAAAUUUUUAAACUUCUCUAAAGGUGUAAUUUGAGUUAAGUAAUAUUGUUUGUUUCUGCCCCCAAAAGGGAGCAACAUGAUGUUAAAACAGAGCAGUUGAGCCUCUCCGCAUCCAACUCCAUUUGGUCAAUUGUCUCCAUUUACAUUCCCUGCCCAAAUCUUUCACCAGCCUUUCCCAUGAUGCCGCAGCAGAUGCCAGACACUGAAGUAGAAAGGGAGCAGCUGUUUCCAAACAUUACUCCAUUGCUGUAUUAUCCUCCACAAUCUGCUUUCUUUUGCUCUCCCCUUCCCCCAUUCUUAAAAUAAAGAAGCCUUCUCUCCCUUUGACUUUUGCAUCCUCCAGUUUAUCAGUGUGCAGGUUUUCUAUCUUAUCAGUCGCACUGGUUUCUUCAGCAGGUCCCUUUAUUGUUUUCGCUAUGGGAGCAGAUGGAGGGCCCUGGGCUCCUGGGGGCGUGGCCGCUGGCACCUCGGGCCCGGGGCUGCGCGUUCCCGACGGGGCGGCGGGGGCGUGCAGCCGGGAACGCGCCCUUCUUCCCGCCAGGGACCCGUUUAUGGCCCUGAGCGCUGUAAAUCUGUCAGCUCUUCACGACGCCUUCACCUCUUUCUUCAUUUGCUCCAGCUUCUAGUUUGACAACGUUCCCCUGAGGCAGAAUUCUAAUCUGCUUCCAAUUAGUUGCAAAAUGUGACUGAAAUUUCCACAUUAUGACUGCUGUUUUACUUGCACGCACACAUCUAGAAACAAAUUAAUGCUCUUGAAUAUUUAUUUUUUGAGCCCUUGGAUUUACUUUAAGAGGAAGAGUUUCCAACUGUUUGGAAUGACUUCCAGGAUUUGCAUUUUUUCCCGAAAGCCGAAUAUACUGGGUACAUUAAAACAAAACAAAGCAACUAUGGUUGCCCCCCAUCACUUAAUAAGACUUUUCCAUCUUUUCAAGAUUUCCCAAAAUGUAUUGCAUAUGUUUAAGUAAUGCAAAUAAAUUUUGUAGUAUUUCUAAAAUAAAACAAGGAUGUUUGGCUAAGGAACGGUCCCUAUGCAGUGUUUUAAUAAAAGAGAAAUAUACAGACACAUUUCCUUCUAAAUAUAGUUUAAGUAUACUUUGGCCAAAACACAAAGACUUUUGUUCCACACGUUUAAAUUCUUUCAUUCAAUAUUCAAAAGCUGUAAACCCAAAUAAACGAAUUGAGUGAUUAAUUGGCUUGGCACAAAUCUAAGGGUAGCAUUAAAUAAGUUACUGUGGGCAUUAAUGUGUACCCAAGUUUUUGUGUAGGUCUCUGGAGCACACCCUCCCUCAGCGAGCGGCUGGGGUGGUUGUACUGAGAUCAGUAUAGUAGGUGGGUUCCUGUGACUUUGGUCUUCCCAGUCCCUCCGUACGCCAGUGUUAGGAGAAUGGACCUAGUUCUGGGCUUCGGGGUGGUUCUGUAUAGAGGGUGAUCAUCACUUAUCACCCCAACUCCAUUUCCUCUCUUUCAGUGAUUUUUUUUAACAAAGAUGUUGAUCCCCCUGAUUAUAUGUAAAUAUUAGAGUUGUUUAAAUCUUGGUUGCUGAGAAUGUCAAGUUAAGACAACCAUUUUAUUACUUGCCUUAAAGACUGCUUUCUCAAGUACUGGAGAAUUUUAGUACCAAGGCAGUGGAUUAGUAUUUGUGAAAAGGUGCUACUCUUAAUGUAAACGGCGAAAUUUACUGGUGCCUUUUAUAGUAGAAUUUAGUCCUCAAGCAUCUUGGCAGAUUGAUAUCAACAGUAAUAAUGGGCUUUAAAGAGGUGUGAAGGAUUUUAUUGAUGGUAAAGUGGUUAUGUUGAUCGCAUCACUGUGUAUUAGUUUCUGAGUAAGAACUGCACAUGUAAAUGGAUGCAUGAGUUUUUUUUAAACAUCUUUAUCAUAUAUAAUCAUAAAACCCUAUAUUGAUUGAUUUCUAAUGCUCUUUUAUGUGCCACUUUGAAUCUCUAAUCAGGAGGUGGAGAAUUUAUUUCAUUUUGUUUCAACAAAACCUAUUCAAAAUUAUUUCUUAGAUAUAUAGGGUAUAUGUUAUUUAAAUGGUUUUCUAAAAACUUAUUUUUAGAUAUGCCAGAAUUCCACAAAAGAAGUCGGAGUGCUCUUUGUAUUGCUUCCUUUCUUCUUACUCAAUGACUAGUAGUAGAAAAAAACAGCCAGAUUGAAAUCCUUAAAAAUUUAAAAUGUUGGGCCUUCAGAUUGCAGAGACCUCCUGGGUUAAAAAAAUGAAAAAAUUAGUGGCCCUGUAGUGAAAUGCUCACAAUAGCAAUGAUUGUGGUAGCCCCUCAAGUCCUGGGGUUCACUAAUUACCCUUUAAUGAGGUCAGUCUGCCCCGGCUUUUUCCCUACCUUGGGAGGAAAAGCACACAAGACAGUUGGAGUUCAAGUGGAUCUUGCUGUAUUUGCAACUUAGCAUAACUGCUUUGAAAGCCCCCAGGGUGCUUAAUUGGGGCCUGGGCAUUUUUGUUUGGGGAGAGACUACACACAGCUCCUCAUUGUGCUUGUAGAAGCCACUGUGCAUCUUGGAAGCAUUACAUGCUUUUGUUGAUGGUGCAUAGUUUUAUAAACUCCAAAUGAGCUUAUUGCUUUUUAACCAUUGGGAGAGCUAAAUAAUGGAAGAACCUAGAAGUCUUUGGGUUGGGUAGCCGCCAAACAGAAAAAAAAAAAAAAAAAAAAAAAGAGAGAGAGAUAGAGAGAAUGAAUGGUUUAAUUGGAGAGCAAACCAUUUGUUUGCAGAUUAAGAUUUACUUGGUCGCCAAAUCCUAUGGAUGAGGUGAAAGAAUGAGGCCGUAAGGUACAGAAAUUGAAUGCCCAGUGUUAUGUUUUGUGAUCAUGCUCAGCUGUUUUUACCCUUUUUUUUUUUCACAAAGAAGGCAAAAGAAGAAUGAAUUGUUUAAUGGAGAGAACUGCCUAGCCAAGUGCAUCUUUUAAGCUGUAUAGAGGGAGGGAAGAAGGUGGGGAGGCAGAUUAUUUCUGUGCUCCCUGGUCAGGAAGCAAAACUCUCAAGGUUCUUUUAGCUGAGAGAGGGGCUAGAAGACUUGCUGAAUCUUCCUGUUUGCUCACUUAAGGAGGAAUGGUGGUGGUGGAGCUAGGGAGUAAAAAGUAGAAGAAAGGUGUGUGGGAAAGAGGGUGGUUGGGGUAGAGCUUUUGUUGCAAGGGCCCUAGACAAUGCAUUCUCUUGAAUAAUUGGGACCAUUUAUAGAAAUUCCCCAUGAUUUCAUUAGUUAGUAGCCCUGUUUCUGAAUAGAAAGGGACUCUCCAGCAACAGCAGUGAAGUGGUACAGCAGUUUUGGAGGGGGAAAAGCAGUUGCCUGGCAGCCUGAAUGUCAGUAUGUCUUUUUUUUUUUUUUUUGAACAAACAAAAAAACCCCUUUCCUAAGGACUAGAAGACCAGAAAUCAUGGCAUUUGUCCAUGUUGUAGUUGCAGUUUGUCCUUCUAAUCUUAUUGUGAAUAAAUAGGUUUCUGGAAAGACCUAGCAUUAUUUUCUAGAAGUAUCAUUCUAAACACUCCUCAACUCACUGUUUUUAUUUUUACUUUAAUCUUGGGAGUGAAACCCUUUAUCUUAAUCUGCUCUUUUGUGUAUAAACUGUCUCUCUUUUUGAUAACUCAGGAUGCAUGCCAUGAAAAAGCCCAUUUCUUCUGUAACAUUAAAAUCAUUUGUUUAUUGAUGCAUAUUUGAUACAUUGAACUUUUAAAUAUCUGAAUUGGCUUUAGGUGAUCUUGUUUUGUUUUUCUCCUAGCUUUAAGUUCUGGUAUUAUUUAUUAUUUUGGUAUCAUGAUCCUUUUGAAAUGGCAUGAUUUUUGAAUCCAAAUAAUGGCUGAUAGCUUCAUUUUAUAGAUCUAUUUCUUCUGAGGGGCGGUGAACAAGAGGAUUGUAGGAAUUGGGGAGCAAAGAGAGUGUAAAAAAUUAGGUCUAAGUAGUUUCAGUUUUGUCAAACUGCUACUUACUUUUUAAUGUGCCAUUGCUCAUUCCUGAUUCUUUCCUGUUAAUAUUUUCCGUAUUAGUGAGGAAAGAGACUGGAUUUUACUUCUGUUAAUGUCUAAAACUCCAAACUUUUUUUUUGUUUUUUGAGAUGGAGUCUUGCUUUGUCGCCCAGGCUGGAGUGCAGUGGCACGAUCUCGGCUCGCUGCAACCUCCGCCUCCCGGGUCCAAGCGAUUCUCUUGCCUCAGCCUCCCGAGUAUCUGGGAUUACAGACACCCACCAGCACGCCUGGCUAAUUUUUGUAUUUUUAGUUGAGAUGGGGUUUCACCAUGUUGGCCAGGCUAGUCUCGAACUCCUGGCCUCAGGUAAUCUGCCCGCCUCAGCCUCCCAAAAUGCUGAGAUUAUAGGCAUGAGCCACCACUCCUGGCCUAAAACUCCAAACUUUUAAAUCUUGUGUCAGUUGGCUGGGCGCGGUGGCUCACGCCUGUAAUCCCAGCACUUUGGAAGGCUGAGGUGGGCGGAUCACGAGGUCAGGAGUUCGAGACCAGCCUGACCAACAUGGUGAAACCCCGUCUGUACUAAAAGAAUACAAAAAUUAGCCAGGUGUGGUGGUUCGCACCUAUAACCCCAGCUACUCAGGAAGCUGCAACAGGAGAAUCGCUUGAACCCGGGAGGCAGAGGUUGCAGUGAGCUGACAUCGUGCCACUGCACACCAGCCUGGGCCACAGAGCGAGACUCCGUCUCAAAAAAACCCAAAAAACAAUAACACUGCCAUAGUCACUAAGUAGACUAAAUUUGUGUAAACACAUCUUUUUAAAGUUAUAAAAAAAAAUCAUGUCUUACCAGUAGGAAAACCUGCAGAUGCUCACCUACAUGUGAUUUCUUUGGUUGACUGAAUGCUCAGUCUAGGUUUACUUAGCAAACCAAAACAAAAGUGCAAAGAUAAACAUGGCUUCUCUUAAUAUUUGUGACAGCCUAGAAGCUUUGCAAUCUUGAAAUUGCUCUACAGUUUUAAUCCUUCCUGGAAAGAAAGCUUUUUACCAAAUUGUCAGUGCCUCCACUCUAUGAAUGCUUCUGAGGAUUUAAAAAACAACCCCCCGAAAUACAAAUUUAUUUCAGUAAGUUUAAUAUGUGCUCACAUGUAGCAUAAAGAAUGGAGAGUAAGUGCUGAGCUUUCGGCCCCUCACAAUUUAAUAUUAACAAGAGUUCUUGUCUCUUGCUUCUCCUCUCUAACCUGUUCUGUAUACUACAGACGUGGAUCCUUUUUGUUGCCCAUAUAAAAUGUGAAAGGAAAAAUGCCAACCUAAGACACUCUGAAAAUGAUUUCUAUAAACCUGUUUACACCAAAGUCUAAUACUCUCUAUCUUAGCUCACAUUAAAGGCUUAAAGUCUCCUUUGAAACACUAGCAUUUGCAUCCGUAAGCCUGCUAUAAAUUCCUGUACAUUAUUUCCUUGUAAAAACCAGUCUUUUCCAUUUACCUGGAGUCAGUACAUCUGCAAGAGUUACUUCCAGCAGAUAAUCCUGUCUAGUUUUAGACUGAUAGAAAUUUUGUAAUAUCUAUAGCUAUAUACUGGUGAUUGGAUGACAACACGAAAUCACUUGCCCUUGUUGGAUUUCAGCUCUGUAAGUAUAUUGGGUCUUAAACAUGUUAAAUUUUCCUUUUUUGACACUUAAAGUAAACUCUGAAGAGGGUGGAAGCCUUUUUACACUUGAAAAAUCUAGAAAAUGCCCUAUGUAUUCAAAUCACAUUGUUGCCAGUGUUUAACACAUAAACACAGAUCUCUUCAAAUCACUUGUGCAUUUGGUGAGCAGCUUGCCAGCACACACCAGUAGUAGGAGGAAGUUAAAUGGUGGUGAAAAAAUAGGUACUGUUUUAUCUUUUGUCUGUAAAAUAAAUUCUGAAAGCUUUUUGAAUAAUUUUACUUUGGAUUUGUUGUUGCUUCAGGAUCUAAGGAAUAAUACUAAUUGUACAAAUCUGUGCAGUGAGGUGUAGUUGCUUCCAUGUUAUUUGAGCCUGAAUGUGCGUGCAUAAUUGGAGAGAUUAUUGGAGAGAGAGUGUUUUGCUGUGGUAGAUGUGGUUUAAAUCCUAGCACUGAGCAUAGCAUUUACUUUCUCAGCUUACCCACAAAAUCUGUGACUAAUUUAGUGAAUGUGAAGAUUUUUGUCCAGAUGGUUAGGUUUAAUUGUAAAAACUGGAAAGAUUUCAAAGUACCCUUUGGGGGAGUGUGGGAAACAACAAGUAAACAACAAAAAAGAAAUAAAAGUAACCACAGAUCACUAAAUAUAGCAUAUAUGUAUAUUUUAUAUUUAUAAACACACAUAGAUAUAUAUACUUAAACAUAUACACAUAUAGAAGUACAGUAUUUACAGUCAAGGAACAGCUUAAAGAAUUUGUUGUAACAGCACGAACCAAUACAACCUACAAGAGGAGUAAUUUUUAAUGUUUAAGGAUUUACUAUGUUCUGUUCUUAAGUGUUUCCUAAAUGUGAGUGUUUAGCCUCUCCCGGGCUCAGAAUAGGUUUCCGCUCCAGUGUGAUACCACUUUGCUGCCACUCGCUAUCCUUGGUUUAGGGGCAUUGUUAGGUACCUCACCAAACAUUAGGGCAAAUGUCCCUCUCACUCAGGACCUCCAUUGGCUGGUCUUCCUCUCUGGGAUGCUCUUGGAGGCCUGGGCUAGCCUGUUCUUCCCAAACUGCAGCUGUGAAGCUCAAAGACGGAGUAAGCUUGUGAAAGGGACAGUGAGAUGGUGAUCAGUGUGCUGUGUCAGGACGAGCCUUCUUUUAAAACAGCAUCCAUUUCUUCUUCACACUUCUUGCAUUUGAUGGCCAUGCCAGAAUGAGUACGGUAAUCAGAACUGAUGCUUUUAAAGCGACUCAGGGACCUCCUCCUUCUGGUUGCUUCCUGUGCAGAUGAGCGCUUAAAGGGCAGAAAUUGGUCUCCUCCCCUUUUGUAAAGUUAGAAUACUGCUGACCUAAAUCUUGGGCCCAUAAAUUAGCUUUUGAAGUUGGUGGGCUAAUAGGGUUCUAUAGUGAAUUUUAUUUAUGUUACUUGGAAUUAUAAGAAGAGAAAGAAGAGUGAUGUGUCAUGGGGUUUAGGAAAUAGGACAGAAGGUGAGGUUAUGGGGCUGUUGAUAAAGUCCGCAUUGUUUAAGUGGGUGGGGUUUAUGGUACUAGAGUCUACAACGCAAGCAACAUGGAUAUAUUUCUUGCACUAGAGUGGAAAUAUGCCCAAAUAUUUAUAAAUCAACAUAUUUAAUAAUAUUCAGGAACUAUAGAGAAUGAGCUAAAUGUAUAUGUAUUUAUCAUAUAUCAAUUGCUGUCAUAUUUGAUUAUUGAGUCUUCAGCAUUUAAAAAUGGCUAAGGAACGAGUUUGAGGUUGUCUUGCAUGGUAACGAAGAUAAGCAGAAGGCCAGACAUGUUGGGAUAGUGAUUUUCAGAUUAUGGAAAAUCUGCGUAAGAUAGGUCAAGAGAAGGUGCUUCCUGUGGAGGAGUGAGUACUGUACAUGUCUGUGAGGCUAUUAUUAUUGCCAGCAGCAUGGGAGAGCUAGAUAAACAAAAUGUCAGCCACCCCAAAGCAGAGGUGAUCUUUGCUUUGAUCCCCUUGGCUAAAUUCCUCCUGAAAAUAUCUUUCUGAUAUGUUCCUAUCCACCUAAAGCCUAUUUUUUUCUCCAUUUAUCAAGAGCUUUGCCCUCCAAUACCAACCUAUUGAAUGACCCUUAAGGUGAUUUUAAGAUAGCACCUCAAUCCCAUCGUGAGUCGACUUUUCAAGACCAAGGUAUGGAAUUCAAAGGUAGGGACUGGUCUAAUAGGAGGAGAGGCAUAAGAGCUUUCCUGGUGUCUUAAAUCACACCUUUGGGCAGUCAUCUCUUCUGCCUAUUUGUAAAGCUGUGUUUGGAGAGAACCUCCUUUACAGAUGUUUCUUAAGAUACUUGGGGCCCGGCACAGUGGCUCACCCCCUGUAAUCCCAGGACUUUGGGAAGCCGAGGCGGGCAGAUCACCUGAGGUCGAGAGUUCGAGACCAGCCCGACCAACAUGGACAAACCCUGUCUCUACUAAAAAUACAAAAUUAGUCGGGCAUGGUGGCACAUGCCUGUAAUCCCAGCUACUUGGGAGGCUGAGGCAAGAGAAUCGCUUUAACCCGGGAGAUGGAGGUUGUGGUGAGCCGAGGUCAUGCCAUUGCACUCUAGCCUGGGCAACAAGAAUGAAACUCUGUCUUAAAAAAAAAAAAAAAAAAAAAAAGGAUACCUGGAGCUGGCAACAAGAUACAACUGAUGAGGCUGAAGCUGUAUCUGAUGUGUGUGGUUUUUUUUUUUUUUUUUUGGUCUGAUUUUUUUUUUUAAGGGACUUUUAUAACUAAGAAGUGAAGUUCAAUAAGGACCUAAUAAGAAAAUGAGAUCUUGAGGAUUGAUACCAUCUUGAGAGUAGUAUAUAUGUUAUAUAUUUCUUUUUUCCAUAUUUGUUAAUAUCUUUUUACAUAUACAUUCAUUUCUAGAAUUUCUGCAUAUUUCUAACAUACCCAAUGAAAUUGAUUUGAGAAAGAGAAAUAAUAGAAGUAGUAUGCAUAAACUGACAAAGAUACUGUGAGGGCAGCUAUACAAGGUCAAGACCAACUGGAAUCCCAAGGACAGAAGUCAGAAAGAUAAUGGAUGUGAUAAACUCAGUACAGCCUGUAUAAGCAGUGAUACUUUUUUAUUUCCUCUGAAGCCUUGACUUGGGGAGAGGAGAGGGUUUUAGAGUUGACAGAGCACAGGGUUGUGAAAUUUUCUAUUGAAAAUCCUGGCACAUUUAGAACACAGUGGAGAAGAAAUUUACUGGAGGAGAUUUGCCCACUUGUUGCAAAACUCUGUUGCUGUCACUGUAAGACCUUUGGUGCUAGGAACUAUAGGUAAAGGGAUGAAGUUGAAGUGUAGGAUCUCACUGUGAUUUUGAAGCUCUGUUACAGGGUAGAGGCCUGUGUUAAGUACAAGCUUGAGAUGGGAGAGAAAGAGCAGAUACAGCAACUGAUGCUGAAUUGAGAGAGGAUCCAAAGCCCGGAAUCCCAGUUGGUUGGAUGUUUGCACUUUUUUUUUGUCUGGAGAUGCUUCCUAGUCUGUUUCUUGACCGACUGCACAUGCUGUUAAAUCCACUCAGGUAACACAUAUGUGUUGGGCGCACAGCCCAUGUCCAGAUUGGACUCGGAGUUGGGCAGAGGCCAGGUCAUGCAGGGCCUUGUAGGCCAUGGUAAGGAAUUUGGAUUUUAGCUUGAAUGCGAUGAGAAACCAUUUCAGAAUUUUGAGCAAGGCAGUGACUUUUUUUUUUUUUUUUUUUUUUAAACAAAUCUUACUGUUGACUGUUGUAUAGAGAAUUGACUGUAGAGAGGCAAGAAGAGGACAAGGGAAAUCAGUUGCAAGACUUUUUCAGUGGUCCUGGUGAGAGAAGAUAGGCUUCUUUGGUAGGCAUGGAAGUGGUGGGAAGUGGCAAGAAAUGGUCACGUUGUCCUGAGAUAAUGAGGAUAUGGAUAUAUGUGGAGUUGUGAAAGAAUGAGAAUUAAGGAAAAUACCUGGAUUUUGGAGGUGGAUGGAAUCAAGAGUUGUGACUCAUUUUUGAUAUAUCCUGUGGCUGCCAAGUGAUUAUGGUCCUUCCACAGGAAGGCCAGGGCUGGAGACACCUAUGGGCAAAUAGGUGGGCUUUAAAGUUAUUGGGCUGGAAGAGGUCACCUCUAGAGUUAGUUCCAAUGGAAAAGACUAGGGCCCAGAGGUGGGCUAUGGAGCAGUAGGAGCCAGCGCCGUGUCCAUUGAGGGGGAAGAAAACCCAGCCAGUCUGGUGUUUCUGGAAAGCAAUGGAAGAAAUUCUAGCAAGGAAGGUGUGAUCAGCUGUGUCAAUUGCUGCCAAGAAGUCAGGUUAAAAUGAGACUCAGAAUUGAUUUUUGGUGACAUUAGCACAAAUCGUUUCUGGGGUAAAGGGUAGUGAUGGGGAAAUAAAAAGUUUGAUUAGAGUGCUUGGAUUUUUUGUGGGAGGUGAGAAAAAACAGGACACUAUGAAUAUAGCACCCUUUUCUAUAAGGGGCAAAGAGAUCAGGGAAUAUCUGUCAUUUUUUAAAGUGGAGAACUCUCACAGCCUGUUUGUAUGCUGAUGGGAAUGAUGAGAGAGGGGUGGAGAAGAGCUGUCCAUACUAGAGAGAGAGAGGAGACAGUGUCCUGAAAUAGGGUGCAUCCAUGGGUCUCUGGAGCUAGGACAGUCCUCCAUUAUAACAGGAGAAAGUCAGAGAAUAUGUACAGAUUUAGGAGUGGUACAGUUUUUUCUAGGAAAAAACUAGAGCGUUUUCAUUUUAUCACUGUGCAGGGUAUUGUUGCUGUGUUAAGGGAUUAAAAAAAAUACACAUGUCAUAGACAGCAGUUAAAUAUUCAUUUCCUUGCCUCCUCCUACAGUUUAGAAGCUUUGGCCAUUUUGUGUUCUGACAGCAAAAAUAAUUAGAAUGGGGGAGGUAUAAAAGCAGGUCUCAAUCUGUUCUUUCAUUUGUUCAUUCCUUUAUUCAUUCCUUACUUUGUUUACCCAGCAAAAAUACCUAGUAAAAAUAUUUCCUCAGCAAACAUUUUUUUGAAUGUCUAUUAUAUGCCUAGCACAGUCUGGGUCCUGGAGGUACAGUAGUGAAGAAACCAAGUCUCUGCUAUCAUGAAGCUUAUAUUCAAAUUUAUUCCAGACAAAUAAAUAUAUUUUGGUUGGCGUUACGUGCUAUAAGGGAGAAUCAAGCAGGAGAAGGUGGUAGAAAGAGAUGGUGGAAAAGAAGAAUUUUAUUUGUUUAUGUUUGAGUAGGGACCUGAGUACAGUUAGGAGCCAUUUGGCCCCCUUGUGGAGGGAACUUUUUAGACCCAGGACCUGUGUACAAUCCCCCCGGGGGUCGAGGAGAGGGAGAGUGUAUUUGGUGUGUUUGAGGAGACACCAGAGUGACUGAAGCUGGAUGAGGGAGAGAGGAGAGUUCCAGAAGAUGAAAUCUAAGAUGGAGCUUGAGGCCAGGCUCCAGAGAGCCUUCCAGAACCAAGUAAGACUCAGAAAGGUGGGAGAGACUGGGGGGCUUUGCGCAGAGGAGGGACAGGCUGUGACUUAAGUUCUAAACGUAUCUCAGUGUGUGGGAACUGAUCCUAAGCUUAACCUCUGGCUUUUGAUUUCAUUCUCAUUUCUCAGUGGUUGAGGGAGAUGAUGUUACCCCGUGUGAAUUAUAUUAACUGAUUUCACAUGCAAGAUCGUAAAUACUGAGUCCUUUUUCAGAGAGUGGACAAAAUGGUACCUUUCUCUGAAGACAUUAAUUGAAAGAGUAUUACUUUCCCCAGAGAACGUAUUCCAGGUGUCUCUGGUUGUGUACACACACACACACACACACACACACGUGCUGUUGAAUUAAUAUAGCUGAUGUUUACUAAAGUUACAAAUAACAAAAAAUUGGAAAUGAUGAGGUAAUAAUAUAAAUAGAAAUGCCAGUCUUUUUUUUUUUUUUUUUUUGCACUCUUUGCAUACUCCCUGGGUUUGACCAUGUCUCCUACUUAGGAGACUGGUCCAGAGCCCUGAGAAAUUAGUUGCAUUUAUUACUUUUUGACUAUUUUUUUUAAAUUAAAAAAAGAGGUCAGAAAUUGGUAAAAGUUCAAACUACACUAAAAUGUUAUAUAAUGAAAAGUAGGUUUUACUUCCCCCUUAUGCCCCCCAGACUGUUCCCUAGAGCCAAUUAUUUUGAACAGUUUUGUAUGUCCUCGAAAUAGUCCCCGUAUGUUCAAGAAUAUAUAUUUAUAUUUUUGUCCCCUUAUACAAAUCACAGCAUAUUAAAGAAACUGAUCUGCACCUUUAAAAUGUUCCUUUGAACAUCUUUGCACAUGUGUGUUUCAAAAUUUAAUUGCCCCCCAACUUGAUUGCAUCCGUUUGCAUUCCCAGCAAUGGUGGAACAUGAAUUGCCUGUAGUUUCUACAAUUUAAUACUGUGAGUUAUAAUUUUCUGGCUUUAAUCUGUGCUAAUCUGAUAGUAAUCUAUUAUUUUAAUUUGCAUUUUUCAUGGGUACAAGCCAUUGUAUUUAUUUUCCUAAAUAUUGAUAAUUUAUAACCUUUGAUUAUCUAGUGAGUUGUUGGCCAUUUCUUAUUUUAAAGUAUUUCAGUGUAUAAUAAUUAAAUAUAUAAUUUUUUCAUGUGUUUUGCAAAUUUUUUUAUGUGCUUUGCAAAUAUUUUUUCCCAUCUCUUCAUUUGUCGUUUGAUUCUGUUUAUGCUGUUCCUCCCCCUACUCCGUGCAAAUAUCUUAAACUGUAUAGUCAGAUUCAUUGAUUGAUGGAGUCAGCGUCUCACUCCAUCACCCAGGCUGGAGUGCAGUGGCACGAUCUCUGGUCAUUGCAACCUCUGCCUCCUGGGUUCAAGUGAUUCUCCUGCCUCAGCCUCUCGAGUGGCUGGAAUUACAGGUGCCCACCACCAUGACUGGUUAAUUUUUGUACUUCUAGUAGAGAUGGGGUUUCACCAUGUUGGCUGGGCUGGUCCUGAACUCCUGGCCUCAGGUGAUCCACCCACCUUGGCCUCCCAAAGUGCUGGGAUUACAGGGGUGAGCCACUGUGCCCAGCCAAACAUUUUUAUUUAUUAACCUUGGAGUAAGAAAUGUCUCCCUAAACCAAUACAAAACCCCUUAGCCAUAAAAGGCAAUGAAUUAUAAAUCUGACUAUAAGGCAGGGCGCGGCUCACGCCUAUAAUCCCAGUACUUUGGGAGGCAGAGGCGGGUGAAUCACCUGAGACCAGGAAUGCAAAACCAGCCUGGCCAAUAUGGAGAAACCUUGUAGCUGGGAGUGGUGUCGCGUGCCUGUAAUCCCACCUAUUUGAGAGGCUGAGAACCGAGAAUUGCUUGAACUGGGGAGGCGGAGGCUGCAGUGAGCCAAGAUCGUGCCACUGCACUCCAGCCUGGGAAACACAGAAAGACCUUGUCUCAAAAAAAAAAAAAAAAUUUUUUUUUUAAAGUCUCCUACUGCUUUUAUGGUAGUUGAACUAUUUUUAUGGUCUUUAACUGGAAGUUAUGAUACAUACCUUCUUGGGUUUGGGGGUCGUAUUUCUACUUAAAUAAUUUUUGAUCCAGUAUACAGAAUUAUUGAACUCUUAAUAUAAAUAUUAUUUCUUAAUCAUAGCUGUGCAUCUGAAUUAUCCGAAGAGUGCUUAAUUGUUUUCAUUUCCACAAAUAUUCAGUCUCAGGCUUCCUAACCCCUAUUCUGAUUCUCCAACUCUAAAGGUUGGCUCCUUUGUAUGCAUUUAGCAAAAGCUUCAGAUAGCUUAUUUGAAGAUAUCUUCUCCAACCCUCAACCCCCACCUCCCUGCCCUUUCUCAAAAGGGAGAUGUUAGGAAUAGUUAUUAGAAUUUCUUGCGUGUGUGUGUGUGUGUGUGUGUGUGUGUGUGUGUGUGUGUGUGUAUUUUAAGGGUUUAUUUAUAGAAAAAUCAUCACAGUAUUGCUUUAAAUAUGACUUCAUUAAGGUGUUUUACAGGUGGUUAAUUAGUGUACUUGGUCAAAUGGGAGGCAAAAGGACUAAUGAUUUGCAGCUCCAGCCCUAGGAAUAUUUACAGCCGGUAAAUACACUUACUGAUGUUUCCCGGAAUCUUAGGGCAGAAACAUCCCUGCACAAAUGAAUUGCUUAAGUAGUAAAGAUGAGCCAUAGCUUUGCUUAGUUAGCCAUUUUGGUUUAGUAGAAUGUAGAUAAUUGCCAUGGAGGCAGGGGGAAACGUUUUGGGAGUGUAUAAAGCAUGAAGUUGUAAGUAUUACUGCUAUAGGUCUGAUCUAUGCAGGUCAUCUCUUCUAGUCAGCUGGGCUUCAGAAAAUUGCCAUGUUGCUCUUGUGCUCUCAGUGUGGAGGUAGCCAGUAAGUCCUGCUGAUGUUGGCCACAUGUGGCCUUUAGGUAGAUUGUUCCCUCCUGCAGACCUUUUACUCUUGAUUUCUACCUGGGUCAUGAUCCAGGGAGAGAAGCUCUAGAACUGGGAAUUGGGGGACUGGUCCCACUUGAUGAUUUGGCUUUGAGUUCUUUUUUUUUUUUUUUUUUUUUUUUUUUUUUUGAGACAGAGUCUCAUUCUGUCGCCCAGGCUGGAGUGCAGUGGUACGAUCUCGGCUCACUGUAACCUCGGCUUCCUUGGUUCAAGCAAUUCUCCUGCUACAGCCUUCCUUCCGAGUAGCUGGGAUGACAGGCGCCCGCCACCUCGCCUGGGUAAUUUUUGUAUUUUUAAAGUAGAGAUGGGGUUUCACCAUGUUGGCCAGGCUGGUCUUGAACCCCUGACCUCAGACGAUCCACCCGCCUCAGCCUCCCAAAGUGUUGAGAUUACAGGCGUGAGCCACUGUGCCCGGCCUGGCUCUGAGUUCUUUUAUGACCCUUGGGCAACAGCUACUGGCUCUGAGCCUUAGUUGCUUCUUGGUUAUGUUGUCUGACUAUCUUUACUGUUCCAAAACAGUUGUAAUUUCCCCCAUUUCUAUUUAUUGCUCUGGAAACACAUGUCGUUUAUCUACACUUUUGCUGUUUUGUUCUGUGGUGUGUGAGCGCAUGUUUCCCCUGCCAGCCUGGAACCCCUGAGGGCAUGGAUGCCAUCUUAUUUGUUUUUAUCUCCCCAGCGCCUAGCACUGAGCCCUCUUACAGGAAAUGCUCAGUCAAUAUUUGUUGAAUUGGAUUCUCUUUUAGUAGGGUUACAGAGGAAAAAAGAGCCUUAAAACUGUCUCCAUGGGGUCCACAUCUUUUGUCUUUUCUUCCAUGUAGAGAUCGUUGGCAAAAACAUUGAUGGGAAUUAUCUAUCUUGCAUUUAUGUGACAUUUUUAAUUCUUUAACAGUAUUGUCAUCUGUAUAAUCAGUUAUAUUGCACCUGGUUUCCCCAGUUUGGUAGAGCAUGCCUAUUGAGUUUUAAAGAAUAAAGAUGACUUAUUCAGAAGGGUCAUGCUCUCAGAAUAACAAACUGUCAUGGCAUCCUGUUUGCAAAAAUCUGCAUUAGGCAGAUUUUUGUCUGAUGAUUUCUUUGUUAUCCACAUGACUUUCAGGGCUAAAAUGAAAUGCUACUUUUUUCUUUAAGUCAUUAUUCAAAAGUAAGAGAGAAGCGUUUAUUAUAACAUAUAGCUUAGGUGUGACCUUGGGAAAGUUGUUUAAACCAAGUUAAUGAUUUAAUUUGCGGGGUGGGGGUGGGGGAGAAGAUAAAGAAAAAGGAAAAAAAAGCCAGCCCAGGAGUUGGGAGUGUAAUUAGAUAUUAUGAGCUCAGGCAUGAAUUUGGCCCCUUUAUCUCUGUUGAAAUUUGUGUAAGAACAUGAAGUGCGGCCCAUUCUGACACUUUAAUCAUAGGUCAUUCAUAGCCAUAAUUGUUGUUGAAAAGAACAGUGGUUGGAUUUAUUUUUACCUGGAAGUUGCCCGUUAAACACAACAUGUUAUUAAAAUUUAUUUUUCCAAAAAGUAUACUUUUCAGUAUACAUUUAACAGAUUGAAGCUAUACAUGUUUACCAUGAAAGUCUGUUUCACCUGAAUGAAUUCCGGUGUUGCUGUGUUAGAUAGCUAUAGCAUGGUUGUGGUUUUUGUAGAGCCUCUACUAAGUUUUAUAUUUCUUACCAUUCACAAUUUUUGCCAGAAAAGUGGUAGAAAAAAGAAACUUCAUAAUCAGAAAGGUGAUAGAGAAACCUCAUAGUCAGAUAUAUUAUAAAAGAAGAUGAUGACACCUAUUAACAAGAAAUCUAACAUCUUUUGUGGUGAGCUUCUAAUACAGUAUCAACAAAGCCUAGGAAGAGUUUCCUUUUUGAGACACCCCGCUUGCCCCCAAAUACAUUCGCUCAGAUAAAUUACUUACUGAGAAGGCUAUUUCUUUUCUAAAAUAAAAAAUACAAUGAAUAAUUUGUAAUCUCUAUACAGUGCCUGGCAUCUAGCUGCCCAAGGAACAUUUGUUGAAUUCAGUAGCACCUUAAAUUAUGUUUAAGUACUUCCAAAGCCAUACUCCUGUUGGUUGUUUUGUUAUUGUUGUUGUUGUUGUUUUGACAGACUUCAACGAUCAUAAGAGAGUAUGUCAUUGCUCUGGCUCACAGGUGAAGAAACUGAGGUUUAGAAUGAAUGCCUGUGCUUUUAGUCUAGCAAAUGUUUAUUGAGUAUGCAUUGUAAUGAAGAAGAAGCACAGCUCUUGCCCUUGAAUUUGCCACUGGGUCAGUUCUCAUCUCCUAGGUAGGUUAGGAUUUUACUGGGCAUGUAUGGACUCUCUCUCCAGGAAAAGGAAGAGAGAAAGUACACAAACGCAGAAACCUUUGCUUCUGUAAUUACAAGGUUUCUGAGGCCCCACAAAUCUUUGAACCCCAGAUUAAGAAUCUUUGAUCCCCACAUAAAGAAUCUUUGAUUUAACCAUUGCUUGUCAACAAGCCCUUGAAUUAAGUAACUGACUUAGGGGGCAAAUAGCUUAACUACUGAGAAGCAAUAGGAACCCCAUGCUUCUUUUUCCUCUCCUAAUGUUUUUCCCACCACCCCAUGCUGAUUUUGAAGUGGUGAACAACAAAUGAAGUAACAGGAAAACACUUUGUAAAUAUAGUGUUCUACAGAUAUGAAUGCAAACAAAUCUGUAAGUGGCAGGGAAACCCAGGCCACACAUUUCGCAGUGUGGCUUAUGUUCAUACAUUAGGGAGCCUGCUGGAACCCCACUAAACUGUUAGUUGCCAGCUGUUUGGUUUAGUCUGAUCAUUUACAAAAAUAUAGCAAUCCUCACUGGUGUGUGUGUUAAAUACAGACAUCACUGAAACGAACGCUGUGCCUGUGACAUACAUUUUUGCAAGUGCUUUCUAUGUAUGGGUUGUCAGAGCUAGUUUAAUUCUAAUUGCAGAAAUAUCAGUGGGAUUUAUAUCUGUCUUCUUCAAAUAGUUGGAAAGAAAAAAUGUAAGCACUUGGCACACAUUUUGAUUUUUGUUCUACAUUGAAAAGAACCAUGUUAAUUUCAAGAAACUCAUUAAUGUGCAGGUCCGUACUAGUAGUUUCUCUUAGUUACAUAUUGGUGGAAGGCAGAAGUAUUAAAAAUGGCAUAUAUGUAAUGAGAUUUUACAAAAUUUCUGAUUUUGAGGGUAGAGAAAAAGCCAGUGGAUUUCCUAUUGUGCAUGUUAAUUUAAAAAUAAUUUAAUAAUGACUCCAUUUGUUUCAUUCCAGCAUUAAAAAGGGACAUGGAGAAGGCUUGCCUGUCUUUAUUCACCAAAUAGCGGUUUUGCAGACCCUUACAAGUUCCCAUAUGCUAGUGAAAAACAUUUUCCAAGAAAUUGGCAGCAUUGCACUUUGUAGCUGAUGCCAGCUUCUUCCUUGGGCCAAUUCAACAGAGAAGAGAGGAAAAAAAAAUGCCUUGUUUUAGUGGCUGAAUUACUCUGACAAGCUUUCACAUCGCCCCUCCUCUUAUUAAUAUUCUUUUUGAUGUGAGCUUGUAAAACAGAGGAUUGGCUGUUAAUCUCCAAGAUCUCAAGGGCUUUUGGCAGUGGCCCAUAAUUGAUGUGUUCACAUGGCUGUUGUCUGACUACUAAUGAUUAGACAGCAGUGUUAUCUACCAGCUAAAUCAGUGUUGCUUAUAAAUCACACUUGAUAAACUGCAGUUUCAUUUCUUCAAAGAGUUCGUACAAUUCUGCAUACUUUGAUGGAAGUGCCAGAGGCAUUUCAUGAUUCUUUGACAGCUUAGAUUAGGUUUAUUUUUCAUUUCUGUUUGACAAAAUAUUAGACUUUUUAACGCAUGUGAAAGAGAAUUUUUUUGUUCCCCUAACAAGGCAUUUAAAGAGUGCUAAGCAGAGAAAGAUGACCUGCUUUCAGUGGGAAGAUGUACAAGUUGGGAUGGCAGGUCCCAGUUUUGCUUUUGCUACCUACUCCAAGGUAAAUGGAAUGGGGCCAUGGCAUCUGGUGCCAUGCCACUUUGAAAGAAGAAGAGAAGAGGCCACCAGCAAGGAAGUUUGCAGAAUGUGGGCCUGUGCUCAGAUUGUGACAGGGUGGAGUAGUGAGAGAGCACCAAUUGCUCAGCCAUGUUAUGUGUUGAGCCCCUGCGUCAAGGUGUGAUUCUGCUUUAUAGACAGGCAAGAGAAAGCAAAAAGGAUUUAUAAGAGGAAAAGGUGCCAGCCAUAGGAUUCAUUUUCCUCCUUCGCUGCCCCUAUAGGGACACUUGCCUGGCCACAGACACACCCAGAGUCCCCCAUCUGUCCAGAACUCUGUGUACUGCAGAGAUGAAACCAGGUUGCAUGUCGCAUGCACAUGGUGGGCUUUGAGAACUUCUGCUAAGUUUUGGGUCUUUAUUGGCUACAAACUCCUGUGGUCUUGAGUUAACUUUCCUCAUUUAUAAAACUAAAACAACAACAAAAAAGGACUAAAUGAUAUCUAAGCUCAUUUUAUUGCUCUUUAUUUUGCAUGUCCUUGGACUGUAUUGUUUCAGAGCCUCAAAAAAGCCUUUUUGCUAACAUUAGUUAAUCUUUGCUUAAUUUUUGAGAUCAAAUAUUAGAUUGCAAAGAAAUGGUUAAAUCAGAAUGGUUUGUGAUUUUUAAAAAAUGAAUUUAUUUAUUUAUUUAUUUAAGGUGGAGUCUCGCUCUGUCGCCCAGGCUGGAGUGCAGUGGCGCAAUCUUGGCUCACUGCAAUUUCCGCCUCUUGGGUUCAAGCAAUUCUCCUGCCUCAGCCUCCCCAGUAGCUGGGAUUACAGGUGCUUGCCACCAUGCCUGGCUAAUUUUUUUUUUUAAUUUUUAGUAGAGACAGGGUUUCUCUAUGUUGGCCAGGUGGGUCUCGAACUCCCGACCUCAGGUGAUUCGCCCACCUAGGCCUCCCAAAAUGCUGGGGUUACAGGCAUGAGCCAUUGCUCCUGGCCAGCAAAAAUGAAUUUUAAAAAUCACAUUUCUUUUAAGAGAAGUUUAUAUAAUUUUAAAAUGUGUCAGAGGGUAAAUAUUUAAUCAAAAUUUACUUUAUUUUGAGAUGGAGUUUUGCUGUUGUCGCCCAGACUGGAGUGCAAUGGUGUCAUCUUGGCUCACUGCAACCUCCGUCUCCCAGGUUCAAGUGAUUCUCCUGCCUCAGCCUCCUGAGUAGCUGGGAUUAUAGGCAUGCACCACCAUGGCCCGGCUAAUUUUGUAUUUUUGUAGAGACGGGGUUUCUCCAGGUUGGUCAAGCUGGUCUCCAACUCCCGACCUCAGGUGAUUCGCCUGCCUCGGCCUCCCAAACUGCUGGAAUUACAGGCGUGAGCCACCAUGCCCGGCCAAAAUGUACAACUUUUACUCAGAAUAAAAUUAUGUUCUGUGACCAAGAUUGGGAGUGGGGCUAAUAAUAACUUAUUAAAGUUUAAAGAGUUAUUAGAGCUCUAGAAUGCAAGAAUGCAGGAGAAUGCACUUAACACUAAAGCUACCUGAAAAAAUUUCACCUAUCCUACCCUACCCCACUCCACCAAAACAAAAGUCAUGUAAGAUUUAACUGAGUACUUCCUUUUAUAUCCAGUACUUUUAGACCUUAAAUCUAGGUGGCAAGUUUAUUUCCCAACUUCCUAAGAGUGGCUUUGACAUGAGCACUACUUUUUCCUAGUAUAUUUUAGGGCUGUAAUUAAAAUAAGCACUAUAGUCAGGGAAUAAAUGUUUAUUGAUAAGUAUUAACAUUGAUGAACAAAGGUGCUUAACUAAGCUGCUUAUUUAAAUGACUUGUGGUUGAAGGAAAUCCCCUCUUUUUUUUUUUAUUAAAUGAAACAAUUUAAAUUUAAGUUGUUUUGGUUAUGGUUAUUAGAUUUUAAUGUGCUAUGGAAAAAUACCCAUGAUUAACUUAGAGAAGAUAGCCAUUCAGUGAUUUAAAUAGAUGCUUCAUUUAGUUUUGAUACGUAAAGCAACUAUAUUAGAGUUUCUUUCUUUUCUUUUUUUUUUUUUUUUUUUUUGAGACGGAUUCUCGCUCUGUCGCCCAGGCUGGAGUGCAGUGGCGCGAUCUCGGCUCACUGCCAGCUCCGCCUCCCGGGUUCAGGCCAUUCUCCUGCCUCAGCCUCCCCAGUAGCUGGGACUACAGGUGCCCGCCACCACGCCCGGCUAAUUUUUUGUAUUUUUAGUAGAGACAGGGUUUCACCGUGUUAGCCAGGAUGGUCUCCAUCUCCUGACCUCGUGAUCCGCCCGCCUCGGCCUCCCAAGGUGCUGGGAUUACAGGCGUGAGCCACCGCGCCCGGCCUAUAUUAGAGUAAUGCAGCUAUAAAAUAUGAGAAAAAUGCAUUAAAAGUUAUGGAGUAUGGUUUUCAUUACGUAAGAUAUGUAUGCAUAAGUAAGGGCUGGUUGGUAAUAUUAAAAAUAAAAAUAAUGAUAACAUUUGAAAAGAUUUUUUACACCACUUAAAAAUAAUAUUUUCUGUUUAAAAGCAGUAUACGUACAUGUAUCUAUGAGCUUUAUGAAGUGUGUAUAUUACCAUUAUGGCAAAAAAUAAGCAUGCAUUUUUUAAUUUUAGAAGAUAAUAGUUUUUCUUGACUGAUUUAAAUCAUGAUUCAAAUCAACUUGAUUUAAAUGUAGUCUAGAUAAUGCUAAAACUAUAUUGCAGGUGUUUGUCAACUAGCUAGAAAUUAUUUUAAUGGUUAAGGGAGUGCAUAAUAGAAAUAAUUAUUUUGCUGCAGAUAUGGCAAGCUCUGUCACCCGUGGGGUGCUUGUACUUGGAUAUUAGACACAUUUGUAAAAAUAAAUAAUAAAUAUUCUGGAAACGUGAUGCCAAGAGAGCGUGAUCCUGUUUACCACCCCUGCUAUCCUUCAUUUCUUUGUGGCAUCAUUUUUUUUUGUGUGUUAAAGAGUAAAUGAGCUGACUUGGUAACUGUGCAAGAAUAAAUGGUUAAUAACAUUUAUUUUUAUUUACAUUUGGGCAUUCUUUUGAGACCAUUUUCAUAGAGGUUGUUUCAUUUAAUUCUUGAAGUACCCCUAUAAAAUAGCUGAGGAAGCAUUUUCAUAGAGUCCAUUUCAUUUGAUUCUUGAAGUACCCCUAUGAAAUAGCUGAAGCAAGCAUUCUUAAUUCUUAUGGAUGUUAACACUAGAAGCAGAAGAUCCUGAUCUCAUUCUUAGGCUGGGAUUUCUCCUAGGAUGUCAGCUUUUAGAAGAAGAAAAAUCACUGUUACCUCCAAAUAAAAUCUUACUAUGUAGUUGGUUCUAAAGAACCUUAAAUAUUCAAUUAUAAAUUCAUCCCCAGGUAUUUUGAAGUGUUUCAUUUAAUUUGAAAACUGUCAUCUGGUUUUCAGAGACUACAGCAGUAUGUUUUUAAUGUGUUGGUUUAGCCAUGUGACAAAUUAAGCAAGCCCUAUGAACAUGUGUUACUGAGAUUGGUAUUGGCAAGGACAAUAAUAACUAACAUUUGUUGAGCACUUAUAUGAUAGAGAUACUACGACGGGCUUUAUGUAGGAUCUCUUGUUUGAUAUGUCUAUUACAUUAAAUACAAUUAGGUAAUACUAUAAUCUCCACUUUAUAGGUGAGGAAAUUGAGGCUUAGAAAGGUUAAGUAAAUUUUCAAGAUUAUACUAGUAAGUAAAUGAUCUGAGAUUGAAGCACAGAGACCACACUCCUAUUUAUUACACUAUAUUACCCAGUUCAAAAGCAUUAGUGAGACAUGUGAUGUGUGACAUUGACCUGUCAUCCUCUGUGAGAAGUAGCUUCUGGGACUGAUGGUCUUAGUUGUGCAUCCAUGACUAGACUUCUGGAUGAAAGAACUCCAAGUUUCUAGGAGGGCUUGUUUCAUUUCUAGUCCUCAACAGAAUGUGUUUGAGAACUUGAUUUUUUCAUGUAAUUCAUUCACUUAUGGGGCAAUUAAGAUAAAAUAUCCUGGUUUUCAAACUGAAAAUGUUACCAAAAACACAUUGCAAUUACAUAGGAUGGUUGUUUCUUCUUUUGGGAAUAGAGACGUAUCAUAGAUUGACAAUGUUGUUUUUUUUAAAAAAGUUUACUUCUUUGUCAGCUCCGUGAAGGGAGGGAUCUUGUCUGUCUUGGUUGUCAUUAGCACCCAGCACAAUGGCUGGUAUAAUAAAAAGAUGUUCAAUAAAUAUUUAAUGUUUUAUGUUAUGACUGCUUAAGUUAGAACUGGAAUGUGGCUCCUCAUAUCUCUUUUGGUUUAUGACUCCUAGGUUUUUUUAAGAGAGUUAGGUAGUAGUAGGUACAUUUAUUAUUAUUUUUCAUUCAGAGAUGGAUCUAUAUGUUUACUUUUAAAAUCUCCUACACUUCUGUCCACUCCCUACUUCCUUUUUCACUUCCUUCCUGCCCUGUUCCAACAUACUGUUAACUUCCCCUCCCCCUCUCCACCAACAGAUAUUAACGUCCAAGAGUGAACCUAAAUGAGCUCUUGAAUUCAGUAGAGCAAGGAUUGGCAAAUUUUUUCUGUAAAUGGCUGAUAGUAAAUACUUUAGGCUUUGCAGGCCAAGAGGCAACAUCACGGAUAUUAUGUAGGCACUUGGAUAACAAGAGAGAAAACAAAUUUCCACAGAAUUUUUUAAUUGACAAAAUUUAAAAUCCAAUGACAAUUAUUGAGCACAAUUUUUGGUAAUACAGAUCUACUGAUGAGAAGUUGACCCCCUGUUUACAGUGCCAGCGCCACCACCGCCGAUUUCCAGCAGUCUCACGCCUCAGAUUCUACCCUCCUACUUUUCCCCAUCUUCAUCCAAUAUUGCAGCACCGGUUGAACAGCUUUUGGUUCGGACUCGUUCUGUGGGUGUCAAUACAUGUGAAGUUGGAGUAGUGACAGAGCCAGAGUGUCUUGGGCCCUGUGAACCUGGGACCAGUGUGAAUUUGGAAGGGAUCGUGUGGCAUGAAACAGAAGAAGGUGUCCUAGUGGUCAAUGUCACGUGGAGGAACAAAACGUACGUGGGAACCCUACUGGACUGCACCAAGCACGACUGGGCCCCUCCCAGGUUUUGUGAGUCACCGACAAGUGACCUGGAGAUGAGAGGGGGCCGGGGCAGAGGGAAGAGAGCGAGGUCUGCUGCUGCUGCCCCGGGCUCCGAGGCCAGCUUCACAGAGUCCAGAGGGCUGCAGAAUAAGAACAGAGGGGGGGCCAAUGGGAAAGGGAGGCGGGGCAGCCUCAAUGCCAGCGGACGAAGGACACCCCCAAAUUGUGCUGCUGAGGAUAUCAAAGCCAGCCCUUCCUCCACCAACAAAAGGAAAAACAAGCCUCCAAUGGAGCUGGACCUGAACUCCAGCUCUGAGGACAAUAAGCCUGGAAAGCGUGUCCGCACAAAUUCCAGAAGCACUCCCACUACCCCUCAAGGGAAACCAGAGACUACUUUUUUGGACCAAGGCUGCUCUUCUCCAGUGUUAAUCGACUGUCCCCACCCAAACUGCAACAAAAAGUACAAGCACAUUAACGGCCUGAGGUACCACCAGGCUCAUGCACACUUAGACCCAGAAAACAAGCUGGAGUUCGAGCCUGACAGUGAGGACAAGAUCUCGGACUGUGAGGAAGGAUUGAGUAAUGUGGCACUUGAAUGCAGUGAGCCAAGCACAAGUGUAUCUGCUUAUGACCAGUUGAAGGCACCGGCAUCCCCUGGUGCUGGAAACCCACCUGGGACCCCAAAGGGAAAGAGAGAGCUGAUGAGCAAUGGCCCAGGUUCCAUUAUUGGUGCUAAAGCUGGGAAGAAUUCUGGCAAAAAGAAGGGCCUUAACAAUGAACUGAACAACCUUCCAGUAAUCUCCAACAUGACGGCUGCGUUAGACAGUUGCUCGGCAGCAGACGGCAGUUUGGCUGCUGAGAUGCCUAAACUGGAAGCAGAAGGAUUAAUUGACAAGAAAAAUUUAGGAGAUAAAGAAAAGGGCAAAAAAGCUACCAACUGCAAAACGGACAAAAACCUCUCUAAACUGAAAAGUGCCCGGCCCAUUGCCCCUGCCCCAGCCCCCACUCCCCCGCAGCUAAUCGCUAUACCCACUGCAACCUUUACAACGACCACCACUGGGACAAUACCCGGACUGCCCUCCCUCACAACAACUGUUGUUCAGGCUACACCAAAGAGUCCUCCGUUAAAACCCAUUCAACCAAAGCCCACAAUUAUGGGAGAGCCCAUCACCGUGAACCCAGCUCUGGUGUCACUCAAAGACAAAAAGAAAAAGGAGAAGCGAAAGCUAAAGGACAAAGAAGGGAAAGAGACGGGAAGCCCAAAAAUGGAUGCCAAGCUGGGGAAACUAGAGGACUCCAAGGGGGCCAGCAAAGAUUUACCUGGGCAUUUUUUAAAGGAUCAUCUCAACAAGAAUGAAGGGCUGGCAAAUGGACUGUCGGAGUCUCAGGAGAGCCGCAUGGCCAGUAUCAAAGCUGAGGCCGAUAAGGUUUACACUUUCACAGACAACGCUCCCAGCCCUUCCAUAGGGAGCGCCUCGAGGCUGGAAUGCAGCACUUUGGUGAACGGGCAGGCACCAAUGGCACCUCUGCAUGUGUUGACCCAGAAUGGGGCAGAGAGUUCAGCUGCAAAGACAAGCAGCCCGGCCUAUUCAGACAUAUCUGAUGCUGCUGACGAUGGUGGUUCUGACAGCAGGUCGGAGGGUAUGAGAUCAAAGGCCAGUUCCCCAUCAGAUAUUAUUUCUAGUAAGGACAGUGUUGUAAAAGGGCAUUCUUCAACUACAGCACAAUCAUCUCAACUGAAAGAGUCCCAUUCUCCCUAUUACCACAGCUAUGAUCCUUAUUAUUCUCCAAGUUACAUGCACCCUGGGCAGGUCGGUGCCCCUGCAGCUGGAAAUAGUGGGAGCACGCAGGGAAUGAAGAUCAAGAAGGAGUCUGAGGAAGAUGCUGAAAAGAAAGACAAGGCAGAGCAGUUAGAUUCUAAGAAAGUGGACCACAAUUCUGCAUCCUUACAGCCUCAGCACCAGUCGGUGAUCACACAAAGACAUCCUGCCCUGGCUCAGUCACUUUAUUAUGGCCAGUAUGCAUAUGGGCUCUAUAUGGACCAGAAGUCUCUGAUGGCCACCAGCCCUGCCUAUAGACAGCAGUAUGAGAAGUACUAUGAGGACCAGAGGCUGGCAGAGCAGAAAAUGGCCCAGACUGGGAGAGGAGACUGUGAAAGGAAAAGUGAGCUCCCCUUGAAAGAGCUGGGCAAGGAGGAAACUAAACAGAAAAAUAUGCCAUCGGCCACAAUCUCAAAAGCUCCCUCUACUCCGGAGCCUAACAAAAACCAUUCUAAACUAGGGCCAUCAGUGCCUAAUAAAACUGAGGAGACAGGUAAAUCGCAGCUUCUCUCCAAUCACCAGCAGCAGCUUCAGGCCGACAGCUUCAAAGCUAAGCAGAUGGAAAACCACCAGCUUAUUAAGGAGGCUGUAGAAAUGAAGUCUGUCAUGGACUCUAUGAAGCAGACAGGUGUAGACCCAACCUCGAGAUUUAAACAAGACCCAGAUUCAAGAACAUGGCAUCAUUAUGUAUACCAGCCCAAAUAUCUGGAUCAGCAAAAGUCAGAAGAACUUGAUAGAGAGAAGAAAUUAAAAGAGGAUAGUCCGAGGAAAACUCCUAAUAAAGAGAGUGGUGUGCCCAGCCUUCCUGUAUCGUUAACAAGCAUUAAAGAGGAGCCCAAAGAGGCCAAGCAUCCUGAUUCUCAAUCAAUGGAGGAGAGCAAGCUGAAAAAUGAUGAUCGAAAGACUCCUGUGAACUGGAAGGACUCUCGGGGAACAAGAGUGGCUGUCUCCUCACCCAUGAGUCAGCAUCAGUCAUACAUACAGUACUUGCAUGCUUAUCCUUACCCACAGAUGUACGACCCCAGCCAUCCUGCAUACCGGGCUGUUUCUCCCGUCCUAAUGCACAGUUAUCCUGGGGCAUAUCUCUCUCCAGGAUUUCAUUAUCCUGUUUAUGGGAAGAUGUCAGGGAGAGAAGAGACAGAGAAAGUCAAUACCAGCCCUAGCGUCAACACGAAAACAACCACUGAAUCUAAAGCACUGGAUUUGCUCCAGCAGCAUGCUAACCAAUACCGCAGCAAGUCUCCUGCUCCUGUGGAAAAGGCUACAGCUGAGCGGGAACGGGAGGCAGAAAGGGAAAGGGAUCGCCACUCCCCCUUCGGCCAGCGGCACCUGCACACGCACCACCACACCCACGUUGGCAUGGGUUACCCGCUAAUCCCGGGUCAAUAUGACCCUUUUCAAGGCUUGACCUCUGCUGCCCUUGUUGCCUCUCAGCAGGUGGCUGCCCAGGCAUCUGCAUCUGGAAUGUUUCCUGGACAAAGAAGAGAAUAACAAGAUUGGACAUGUACAUUGUCAUGUGACUGGAUCACAUGGGGAAGCGCUUUAUACAGACAUCAGUUCCAUGGUGUUAAUUUGAAAUGCCUUAAUGGCAGGCAAAAACCAGUCAUUUCAUUUUUGUAAAUUACAGAUUUUAUCACAGAGUAACAAAUGUUGCUGUAAUUAAACUUCUGUUUUAUAUAUAUAUACGUAUACAUAUCUGUAUAUAUACAUAUAUAUAUAUAUAAAUAUAAAUAUAUUCUUUACUUUUUGUAUCAGUAACCAGGCUCGCACACACAGGGUCUGCUGCCACGUCGCAAACCACUCAGUAAAGGAAAUUAAAAAUGUAUUUGUCAUGUUAAAAAGUGUUAGCCACAAAAGGCUACUUACUUUCUUUUCCUUUUCCUUUAAAAUUGUAAAUAAAUAAUGUUAUGUAUCAGUGUGCCUGAACCUUGCAUAUCCUUCACAUAUUUCCCAUAAGCCCCUCAGAAAGGCUAACUGUGAUGAUGACACUUUGGUACAAUUUAGAUGUCUAUUUGGUGGCUCCUGUUAAAGACGCACCAGUGUAAAAUGUUCCUGUAGUCACUGUUUGUACUUGUGUAUUGUGGAAAAAGUACUUUUGGAAGGCAUGGGGUUGCCAGUACCACAAAAACUGUGUUGUAUAUAAUGUAAAGAUUAAAAUGGGGAAAUAAUGAGCAUCUGUGAAUAAUGAGGUGUCAUUUUUUGAUAAUCUUGAAUGGCAAAUAACCCAAUAGCCUGCGUACCAGAGACAUCUGUGAUUGUUCUAUUACUUGAAUAGUUCUACAGUCUUUUUUUUUUUUUAAUGUUUACAAUUAUCCAGUUUUAGAAGAGAGAGACUUUAACGCCAUUGCCUGGUUACUUGUUUUAUGCUGUAAUCUAGUUUAUUUUAUGUAAAAUGUAUAUUGAAUGCUUUCCUUUUUUAUACCUGCCUUAAAUAAUUUGGCAAUCAGAAUUAAAAAGUUUUUUUUUUUUUAAAUAA